AGCCUUGCUCCCGCCCCCGCCGGUCCCGCGGUCCCACGGCGCCUGGUUGCCCCCAGCCCCCUCCCUCCUCCCACCUUCACUGUGUCCCACCCUUCCUAGCUUUGUGCCCGGGGUGCUGAGCCCUUCCCCGUCAGCCGGGCCGCGGGAGGAGGGAGCCGUCACCGAGGAGCUGCCGCUCGCUGCCCCGGGCAGGGGCACAGGUUGAUGUCAUAUUUUUAGUCUUGAGAAACAGCAUCAUGCCAAGGAAAGAGCUUGAGCUUUGGAGUAAUGCGGCCCUGAGAUUGAAUUCUGGCUCUGCCACUUAUUAGCUCUGUUCUAGAUUGCAACCAAGGCAAUGUCUUACUACCUCAGCUCAGAAAACCACCUGGACCCAGGGCCCAUCUACAUGCGAGAAAAUGGGCAGCUGCACAUGGUCAAUCUGGCUCUGGAUGGUGUCAGGAGUAGCCUGCAGAAGCCAAGGCCUUUCAGACUGUUCCCCAAAGGCUUUUCUGUGGAGCUUUGCAUGAACAGGGAAGACGACACUGCACGGAAAGAGAAGACUGAUCAUUUCAUCUUCACAUACACCCGAGAGGGGAAUCUUCGGUACUCCGCCAAAUCCCUCUUCAGCCUUGUCCUGGGUUUCAUCUCCGACAAUGUGGAUCACAUUGAUUCCCUUAUUGGCUUUCCUGAGCAGAUUGCUGAAAAGCUGUUCUCUGCUGCUGAAGCCAGACAGAAAUUCACUGAGCCAGGUGCAGGGCUGAGGGCUUUACAGAAAUUCACUGAGGCCUAUGGAAGUUUGGUGCUUUGCUCCCUGUGUUUGCGAAACAGGUAUCUCGUGAUUUCAGAAAAGCUUGAGGAGAUUAAGUCUUUCCGGGAGCUGACCUGCCUGGAUCUUUCCUGUUGCAAGCUUGGAGAUGAGCAUGAACUUCUAGAACAUCUCACCAAUGAAGCCCUGUCUAGUGUAACUCAGCUCCACCUGAAGGAUAAUUGUUUAUCUGAUGCUGGGGUGCGGAAGAUGACAGCACCAGUUCGAGUGAUGAAAAGAGGCCUUGAGAAUCUAACAUUAUUAGACUUAUCAUGUAACCCUGAGAUCACAGAUGCAGGCAUUGGAUACCUCUUUUCUUUUAGGAAACUAAACUGCUUAGAUAUCUCUGGGACAGGGCUCAAGGACAUCAAAACCGUCAAGCACAAGCUCCAGACCCACAUAGGCCUUGUUCACUCCAAAGUGCCUUUGAAGGAAUUUGAUCAUAGUAACUGCAAGACAGAGGGCUGGGCUGACCAGAUCGUUCUGCAGUGGGAGCGUGUGACUGCGGAAGCUGUGAAGCCACGGGAGACCUCGGAGCCUAGAGCAGCAGCUCAGCGCUUCUAUGGGAAGCGGUCUCGAGCAGAAGCCCCACUGAAGUGUCCCCUGGCAGACACCCACAUGAACUCUUCCGAGAAACUCCAGUUCUAUAAAGAGAAAGCCCCAGAUUGCCAUGGGCCAGUGUUGAAACACGAAGCUAUCUCAAGCCAGGAGUCAAAGAAGAGCAAGAAGAGACCUUUUGAGGAGUCAGAGACAGAACAGAAUAACUCUUCACAACCUUCAAAGCAGAAAUAUGUAUGUCUUGCUGUGGAAGACUGGGACUUGUUAAAUUCCUAUUGAUUAGUAGAUACAAGUUGACCUUUCUCUGGCCCCCAGCUCUAGUGUUUGAGUAAAGGAGACUGAGGAUGAUUUACUUUUUGUUUGAAUUUACCUAUGGCAUUAGCAUAGUAAGCAGAUAUUUCUACUUUUGUGGUGUGGGAGGGGAAUGCUAUGGAAGUAUGUAAUAAUUUCUAAUGUAUAUUUUCAAUACAUAGUAAUUUUUUCAAAUAAACAUUUUUGCUGUCCUUAA